GUGGUUCUCGUGUUGCUGCAAUUUGAUGCGAGGAGAUGUCUGGACGAGGGAAGCAGGGAGGAAAAGCACGCGCCAAGUCUAAGUCUCGCUCUUCUAGAGCGGGUUUGCAGUUUCCCGUAGGCCGGAUCCAUCGUCUGCUUCGUAAGGGAAACUAUGCAGAGCGGAUAGGGGCAGGCGCACCAGUGUAUUUGGCGGCAGUGUUAGAGUAUCUCACAGCAGAAAUCCUUGAGCUGGCAGGCAAUGCGUCUCGCGAUAACAAAAAAACUCGCAUUAUUCCCCGCCACCUGCAGCUAGCGAUCCGCAAUGAUGAGGAACUCAAUAAGCUUUUGGGCGGCGUGACCAUUGCCCAGGGCGGAGUCCUGCCUAACAUUCAGGCAGUGCUGCUGCCCAAGAAGACUGAGAGUCACCACCAUAAAGCCCAAAGCAAGUAACUUAAGGUUGUCAUUGGUAAAAAGACUUCUGUGUCAGAAAAAACAAAAGGCUCUUUUCAGAGCCACCUA